GGUUUCGCUCUUGUUGAGGCUGGAGUGCAAUGGCGCAAUCUCCCGGGUUCAAGUGAUUCUCCUGCCUCAGCCUCCUGAGUAGCUGGGAUUACAGGCAGGCACCACCACGUCUGGCUAAUUUUGUGUUUUCGGUAGAGAUGGGGUUUCUCCAUGUUGGUCAGGCUGGUCUCGAACUCCCGACUUCAGGUGAUCCGCCCGCCUCAGCCUCCCAAAGUGCUGGGAUUACAGUCAUAUUUGAUCAGAAAUUGGAUGAACCUUCGGGAUGCUGAGACAGGGAAGAUACUCUGGCAAGGAACAGAAGACCUGUCUGUCCCUGGUGUGGAGCAUGAAGCCCGUGUUCCCAAGAAAAUCCUCAAGUGCAAGGCAGUGUCUCGAGAACUUAAUUUUUCUUCGACAGAACAAAUGGAAAAAUUCCGCCUGGAACAAAAAGUUUACUUCAAAGGGCAAUGCCUAGAAGAAUGGUUCUUCGAGUUUGGCUUUGUGAUCCCUAACUCCACAAAUACCUGGCAGUCCUUGAUAGAGGCAGCACCCGAGUCCCAGAUGAUGCCAGCAAGCGUCUUAACUGGGAACGUUAUCAUAGAAACAAAGUUUUUUGACGACGAUCUUCUUGUAAGCACAUCCAGAGUGAGACUUUUCUAUGUUUGAAAGAAGAAUGUGUGUACAUUUCAAGAAUUUGGGUUUUUUGGAGGGAGGAGGAAACUGUUUACUUUUUUCCUCCACACGUUUGAUUUUUGACACAUACACCCCUAAUUCCCUCAACAGCAGAACCUACCUGCAGCCACCAGGGGACCAGCUCUGUGUAGGUAACCAGAUGGCUCUUUUUCCCAAGCCACCAUCUUCCAGCUGACCAGACUAAACUCCCAACCCCAGACCAGGGCAGGGGACAGGUCUCAAGUCCUUCCCAGCAUACACACAGGGAACAAACACAUACCACAAACCGGUAACUGUACCUGUCACCCUCCUUGUCUCCUCCUUGGGCCCUACAGGCUACACAUCUACCUUUGGCCCCUGGUUUUGGAAAAAUUCCGUGUUCCUGACCCAUGUUUAGUUUUUUCCUACCAUUUCUAUUUCAUACAUUCUCAUACAUUUAACUUGUAAAAUAGACUGUGAUAUUAUUACAUAAUGUAAUUAAAAAUAUGAAUUAAAAUAUUCCUACAGUCUUUA